GGGUCACGUGAGCGGAAAAUGGCGGCCCCGGCAGGCGGCGGAGGCUCCGCGGUGUCGGUGCUGGCCCCGAACGGCCGGCGCCACACGGUGAAGGUGACGCCGAGCACCGUGCUGCUUCAGGUUCUGGAGGACACGUGCCGGCGGCAGGACUUCAACCCCUGUGAAUAUGAUCUGAAGUUUCAGAGGAGCGUGCUCGACCUUUCUCUCCAGUGGAGAUUUGCCAACCUGCCCAACAAUGCCAAGCUGGAGAUGGUGCCCGCUUCCCGGAGCCGUGAGGGGCCUGAGAACAUGGUUCGCAUCGCUUUGCAGCUGGACGAUGGCUCGAGGUUGCAGGACUCUUUCUGUUCAGGCCAGACCCUCUGGGAGCUUCUCAGCCAUUUUCCACAGAUCAGGGAGUGCCUGCAGCACCCCGGCGGGGCCACCCCAGUCUGCGUGUACACGAGGGAUGAGGUGACGGGUGAAGCUGCCCUGCGGGGCACGACGCUGCAGUCGCUGGGCCUGACCGGGGGCAGCGCCACCAUCAGGUUUGUCAUGAAGUGCUACGACCCCGUGGGCAAGACCCCAGGAAGCCUGGGCUCGUCAGCGUCGGCUGGCCAGGCAGCCGCCAGCGCUCCACUUCCCUUGGAAUCUGGGGAGCUCAGCCGCGGCGACUUGAGCCGUCCGGAGGACGCGGACACCUCAGGGCCCUGCUGCGAGCACACUCAGGAGAAGCAGAGCACAAGGGCACCCGCAGCUGCCCCCUUUGUUCCUUUCUCGGGUGGGGGACAGAGACUGGGGGGCCCUCCUGGGCCCACGAGGCCUCUGACAUCAUCUUCAGCUAAGUUGCCGAAGUCCCUCUCCAGCCCUGGAGGCCCCUCCAAGCCAAAGAAGUCCAAGUCGGGCCAGGAUCCCCAGCAGGAGCAGGAGCAGGAGCGGGAGCGGGAUCCCCAGCAGGAGCAGGAGCGGGAGCGGCCCGUGGACCGGGAGCCCGUGGACCGGGAGCCGGUGGUGUGCCACCCCGACCUGGAGGAGCGGCUGCAGGCCUGGCCAGCGGAGCUGCCUGAUGAGUUCUUUGAGCUGACGGUGGACGACGUGAGAAGACGCUUGGCCCAGCUCAAGAGUGAGCGGAAGCGCCUGGAAGAAGCCCCCUUGGUGACCAAGGCCUUCAGGGAGGCGCAGAUAAAGGAGAAGCUGGAGCGCUACCCAAAGGUGGCUCUGAGGGUCCUGUUCCCCGACCGCUACGUCCUACAGGGCUUCUUCCGCCCCAGCGAGACAGUGGGGGACUUGCGAGACUUCGUGAGGAGCCACCUGGGGAACCCCGAGCUGUCAUUUUACCUGUUCAUCACCCCUCCAAAAACAGUCCUGGACGACCACACGCAGACCCUCUUUCAGCCCCAGCUUGGUGACCGGGUGGCUCCAUUCACCCUGGGUCCCUCGCUGAAACGGUGCCUGGGACCAGAGCAGAGAACACGCUUGCCAGUGGUAGGAGAUGGAGGCGACGUGGACUCUGGGAGGCUUCUUUUUUGGGGUCCAUCCAGAGGCCGAGCCUCUCCAAGCACUGGUCAGCCUCCAUGCCACCCAGUCUGCCGACCCUCCUCUCCACCAUCCCCUCGUCCGAGCAGUGGCGAUCCCUCCCGAGUCAAGGCUGGGCACAAGCACGUGGGGACAGGCCGGGCGAACCUCUUCCCGGCCGCUCUGGUGCACUUGGGAGCCGAGGAGCCGGCAGGUGUCUACCUGGAGCCUGGCCUGCUGGAGCAUGCCAUCUCCCCAUCUGCGGCCGAUGUGCUGGUGGCCAGGUACAUGUCCAGGGCCGCCGGGUCCCCUUCCCCAUUGCCAGCCCCUGACCCUGCACCUAAGUCUGAGCCAGCUGCUGAGGAGGGGGCGCUGGUCCCCCCUGAGCCCAUCCCAGGGACGGCCCAGCCCGUGAAGAGGAGCCUGGGCAAGGUGCCCAAGUGGCUGAAGCUGCCGGCCAGCAAGAGGUGAGAGCUGCCAGCCUGAGGUGCCCACUCCGCCAGCCACAGGACCACCUCCUCUGCCAGCAGGAAUAAAGACUUGUGCAUCCCUCAA